AGAGGCCAAGUGGGCACCGGAUAGCGCCAGCCCCGCCCAGGUGAGCGCUGAGGUGGGAUUGGAAGAGGGUGGCUAGGAGGGGCCCUACUUUCUACCCACUCCUAGCCCCCUUUCUCAGGACACCGCCUUUCUUCCCACCCUCCUCCCUGCCCACCUCCUCCAGGCAGGCUUAUACCCCAGCUGAUGCUUUUGGGCAACAUAUCCUGUCCCUGAGAGUUUAGAGGUCAUCUGUUCGCACCCCCUUUCACUCUGGAACCCUGAAACCAGUUACCUAACCUCUCUGUGCCUUAUUUUUCACAUUUAUAAAAUGGGGGUUCCAACAGGAACUCAUUCUUAGGGAAGCUGUGGGGAUUAAAGGAGAAUGCGGUUCUGCUGCAACCACAUGGGGAUAGCCAGUGUUCCCUGUCUGUUGCCUUUUUAAAUUGGGGAAUGGGUAUAAUAUAGCAUUUAUAUCAUGGGGCUGUUGAGAGGAUUAAACAAGCGUGGAAAGCUUUCAGAAAAGUAAGCAGGUGGUCAGUAUGGGUGGGACAUGGUCUCACAGCCAGGUCUGUCUGACUCCAGGCCCAGUGCUUCCUCCCAGGAGUCAGAGAGCGAAAUCAUGGAGCCUUCCAAGACCUUCAUGAGAAACCUGCCAAUCACACCAGGCUAUAGCGGCUUUGUGCCAUUCCUCAGCUGCCAAGGAAUGUCCAAGGAGGAUGACAUGAACCACUGUGUGAAAACCUUCCAGGAGAAAACACAGCGCUAUAAAGAACAGCUGCGGGAAUUGUGCUGCGCAGUGGCCACUGCCCCGAAACUGAAACCUGUCAACUCCGAGGAGACGGUCCUGCAGGCCCUGCACCAGUACAAUCUGCAGUACCACCCCCUGAUCCUGGAAUGCAAAUAUGUAAAGAAACCUCUCCAGGAGCCCCCGAUCCCUGGCUGGGCAGGCUACCUGCCGAGAGCCAAGGUCACUGAAUUUGGCUGUGGCACGAGAUACACUGUCAUGGCCAAAAACUGCUACAAGGACUUCCUGGAGAUCACGGAGAGGGCCAAGAAGGCACAUCUGAAACCAUAUGAAGAAAUAUAUGGAGUUAGCUCCACAAAAACUUCUGCUCCGUCUCCAAAAGUUUUGCAGCAUGAAGAGCUGCUGCCAAAAUAUCCCGAUUUUUCUAUUCCAGCAGGCACCCUGACCUCCCUCAGCAACCACCCGUAUGCAGAAGAAAUAACAGCUCCUGGGACAAUGAGACCGUUGUCAUCCACUCAGAAAUGUGCAGAGCCACACGAGGCAGCAAGCUGGGCCUCGGAGGUUUUUUCCAAGGCAAGAAUUUUCACCUGGACAUGCUGGGCUCCCAUGAUUCCAUGGGUAGAAGUCAGAAGGUCAGAGAACUUUGAUGAGAAAAAAAGUUACAUCAUUGUUUUCACUAACCUCCAGGCGAAAUUUAGUAUUUCCUUCCUUGAUGAAUGCAGGCAACAAACCACUGCAGGACCUGUCACCUUGGCCUGAGAGCAGUCACAGAUGUUUUUGUAUCACGUGGCUCUGGCUGCAAACAGCUGGAAUGAUGUUAAAGCUCAUCUCUGUAAUCAUGGUGGUUAUUACAGUGACUAUAUCUACUCUCUCACAUAGUGUUAUUCAAUAUAAGAAUAAAGAAAUGGCUGUUUUAUAAA